AGUGUGAGAAGCAGUAUGUGUGAGCAUGUGUGUGUGUGUAUGUGUGUGGGGGGGGGUGUAAAAUGUGUUUUUCAAAGUACUGAGAGGUUGAUGGGACUGUUCGAUUAGCUCCUCUGAGAAGAAGAGAAAAGGUUCUUGGACCUCUCCCUGUUUCUUCCUUAGAAUAAUUUGGAUGGGAUUUGUGAUGCAGGAAAGCCUAAGGGAAAAAGAAUAUUCAUUCUGUGUGGUGAAAAUUUUUUGAAAAAAAAAUUGCCUUCUUCAAACAAGGGUGUCAUUCUGAUAUUUAUGAGGACUGUUGUUCUCACUAUGAAGGCAUCUGUUAUUGAAAUGUUCCUUGUUUUGCUGGUGACUGGAGUACAUUCAAACAAAGAAACGGCAAAGAAGAUUAAAAGGCCCAAGUUCACUGUGCCUCAGAUCAACUGCGAUGUCAAAGCCGGAAAGAUCAUCGAUCCUGAGUUCAUUGUGAAAUGUCCAGCAGGAUGCCAAGACCCCAAAUACCAUGUUUAUGGCACUGACGUGUAUGCAUCCUACUCCAGUGUGUGUGGCGCUGCCGUACACAGUGGUGUGCUUGAUAAUUCAGGAGGGAAAAUACUUGUUCGGAAGGUUGCUGGACAGUCUGGUUACAAAGGGAGUUAUUCCAACGGUGUCCAAUCGUUAUCCCUACCACGAUGGAGAGAAUCCUUUAUCGUCUUAGAAAGUAAACCCAAAAAGGGUGUAACCUACCCAUCAGCUCUUACAUACUCAUCAUCGAAAAGUCCAGCUGCCCAAGCAGGCAAGUGCUCACGUGUGAUUGAAUCUAAACCUUCUGAGUCCAUGAACACGCGACGUGUUUUGGGAGAUAGCGGAGAAAUUAACAUCUUAACCGGUCAAGCUCCACUGGCUCUGGCAAUAUUUUAACAGAUGCCAGGAACAUGGGCACAGAAAUCAAUGAGAUCAGAUGGCUGGGGCUGAAGAAUGAAAGCUUUAUUUUUUGUUUUUGCAAUUCCGAGAUUGUGUCUCUAUAUUUGUGUCAUUUUCAUUCAGAUUGACUGUUGCCUUGAGUUUUAAUGUAUUGUUGCUUUAGAAAAUGACAUGACAUUCUGUCCGGAAAUGUUUCCUGGCAGCUAAAAGGAAAAAGCUGUAUCUACUUAGAUAUGAAAUGAAGAGAAGCAAAGAGAACGAGGUGGUUUAUGUGAUAACAGCAAGCUGCUCAUCCAAAUAACCCAGGCCAAAAAUACACUGUCUACAAGGUUGUGCCAACUCAGCUUUCAUGUGAACCACAAAAGGGAGUAUCGGUAGACCUCAGGCCAAGAAAAUACCUUUUUCCAGGUUUCUGUGUUAAAUCAAGAACUGUACUAUGCAUUAUUGUAUCUCCAGAGGUGUUUUGAUUUCCCACACAAAGAGAAACUGUGAGUCGCUUUAUAACGGGAUUUUGCAUUGCUUCCAGAAACUUGAUAGGCUAGCUAAUACAUUAUGAGCCUGAUAGUUCAGGUUCUGUUCAUGUACUUAAGGUGAACACGGUUUAAGAAUAGCAGUAGAACUUAGCAUUUAUUGAGCAUUUGCUGUAUGCCAGGCAUCAUUCCAAGAAUUUUACCUGAUCAUUGUGUUUAAUCACCGUAGACCACCAUCGGCCUAUACUAUUACUCUGGCUGAGGAAAAUGAAGCACAGAGAAGUUAAGUAAAUUAACUUCCAUCAAACAGAAACCCCUCUCUAAACCACCAUUCUAUAUUUUCUUUCUCUUUUUUUUUUUUCUUUUUUUGAGACGGAGUUUCACUCUGUUGCCAGGCUGGAGUGCAGUGGUGCGAUCUCAGCUCCCUACAACCUCUGCCUCCCAGGUUCAAGCGAUUCUCCUGCCUCAGCCUCCCGAGUAGCUGUGACUACAGGCACCUGCCACCACGCCCGGCUAAUAGUUGUAUUUUUAGUAGAGACGGGGUUUCACCAUGUUGGCCAGGAUGGUCUCGAUCUCUUGACCUCAUGAUCCUCCCGCCUCGGCCUUCCAAAAUGCUAGGAUUACAGGCAUGAGCCACUGUUCCUGGCCCAUUCUAGAUUUUCUUAUGCUAAUAGUACGUAUAUAGAUCGCUGAUUUCCUGAUUUGAGGAGCCUUAGCAUACAAAUAAGGAAUUUUUUUUGUCUUUUCUCUUAAUUACUGCUCCACCUCUAUCUUUAAUUACUUUUUAAUGGAUCCAGUGGUCUAGUCCUGUUUGUUUAGUUUCAAGGAUAGAGCUGUUCCCCACCUCCACCCGUGAACUGGCAGUGGGUCUGGUGCCUCGUGGGCCAUUUCUGAGAUAUCGCUUGUCCUCUUUUGACCUGGGCACAGAGACGAAGAAUGGGUGACAGGUCUCCUUAAGUGGCUGGCAUCUCUGUUGUUUCAUCUGGCCCUGUGGCUCUGCAGAGCCAGAGGAAAGACUGAUUCCUGGGUAGGUGAUGUGUGUAGAUAUCGAAGGCAAGGAGACAGUGUUUAGUUUCAUCCUGGCACCCUCUUGUUGGGCCAGAAAUCUGUGCCCCUCACUCCUUUCUCCAAGGUAGAUACGGAUGCCUGGUUCCAGCAGCCCCCUGGGGCAGCCCCUUCCCACAGAGCCAUGGGAACAGCCAGGCUUCUCUUUGGCACCCUCAGGUCUGAGAACUGGGAUGGGGUGAGGUCACCUCCCUCCUCGCAUUUUGCUGCAUGAGCCCUGCUGGCAUGAGCCACUCCAGCUGCACCCCUCCCCCUCUCAGAGAUCCCUAGGGCAGAAACAGUCCCCAGGUUCACAUAAAGCCCCCAACUUCAGGGACCACAUGUCAAGCACCCCCUAUUUUUACCAUGAGUGGAAGAGCACUUCUAGACUCCCAGAAUACACCCCCAAAACUCUGCGAGCUCUGUUGCUGUAUUGCACACGUGUGAUGGAUCUGCAGAAAGAUUGGUUGGAAAUAAGAUGCCCACCUGCCCUCCUGGCAGGUCCCCACAAUCUUGACGAAUGACUCUCUUAAAGCACCUUCAUUUGGCUUGGGUACGACAAAGUGUGAAGGAAGGGAGAAAAUAUCUUCUGACUGUGAACUCAGCACCCUCUAAAAGGUGGCUUCUGACCCCUCCUGUUUUUCGGGUCCUUUCCUUCUGUCCACUGGCCUGGGAUGGGGGUGUCGGGGGUGUUGUGCAGGUUCUACUGGAAUGGCCUCACCCGUGGGAAGUUCAGUGGCAUCUCUCCUGUUUUGGAAAGGGGUACUUGUGGCCGGGCGCAGUGGCUCACACCUGUAAUCCCAGCACUUUGGGAGGCCGAGGCAGGCGGAUCGCGAGGUCAGGAGAUGGAGACCAUCCUGGCUAACAUGGUGAAACUCCGUCUCUACUAAAAAUACGAAAAAUUAGCUGGGCGUGGUGACACGUGCCUGUAGUCCCAGCUACUCGGGAGGCUGAGGCAGGAGAAUCACUUGAACCCGGGAGGUGGAGGUUGCAGUGAGCCAAGAUCACGGCACUGCACUCCAGCCUGGGUGACAGAACGAGACUCCAUCUAAAAAAAAAAGAAAAAAGAAAGGAGUACUUGUGCCCUUCUGGCUUCAGCUUUGGGCCGUAUCUGGACAGCAGGAAGGGCCACAUAACCUUCUGUGACUGUAGUCGUCUGUCCAGUACUUUCUCUGUGCCACACACCUGCACUACAGUAACCCCGAGGUAGAGUGCCAGUAUCUUCCCUUUUCAGAUAAGGAAGCUGACCUUGAGAGAGGUUUAGUAACUCACCCAAGGCCAUAGUUCUAAGCAGCCCAAAAAGUAUGCAAACUCGGUAUCACCUUAAAGCAGGGAAAGUUGCAGGGAAAAGAGUGUAGGGCAGAGAAACUAUAGCCAAAUGAUAACUCGGAUAAUAAAAGUCUACUUGGUUUGUACGUUCUCCGCAGCAGAGACAAUUUCUAAAACUAUCUAUUUACCCCAAGCACCAUUCACCCCCAGCAAGCACUUGUUCCAGAUGCCUGAGUCAUUGACAUCCACAAGGAGUGUGGAUAGCCAAGGGUGCUUUUCGUGAAAUUUAUAAACUAGCAAGAGCCAAGCAUUGCUGAUGUCACUUGCCCCUUUACCAAACCGUUUAAACUUUUGAUGACAGUAUCACUAGGCAUUACUAUCAUCUCCUUGUUACUAGAUGAUCUAUGAUGGUCAGAGUCGGAAAAAUUAUUUACUCCUUCAUUUUAUUCAUUCAUUCAAUGUUUACAUUGAGUGAGCAUCUCCUACGUGCAAGACCCUGAGCUAAACUACCAGCAUUCCAACAUAAAAGGGAUUCUUGGGGAUAGAAGAGCCUCUCUCUGUAAAGUCUUAGUCCCCAAGUCCUAAGUCCUUAGUCUUACUUAGGAGUAAGUUUUCACGAAUUCAAAUAAAAAAUUUCAAUGAGUACAAUUAAA